AUUGUGACCAGAGGGGUUUGUGUGGCUGAAGAGGCAGGAGGAACAGUGUAUCCACAGCGUGGGACCAUGCCAGGCACAAAACGGUUUCAACAUGUCAUUGAGACCCCGGAGCCUGGCAAGUGGGAGUUGUCUGGGUACGAGGCAGCUGUGCCAAUCACGGAGAAGUCAAACCCACUGACCCAGGAUCUAGACAAAGCAGAUGCUGAGAACAUUGUUCGACUGCUAGGGCAAUGUGAUGCUGAGAUCUUCCAGGAGGAGGGGCAAGCCCUGUCCACAUACCAGAGACUCUACAGCGAAUCCAUUCUGACCACCAUGGUACAGGUGGCUGGGAAAGUUCAGGAAGUGCUGAAGGAGCCAGAUGGGGGGCUGGUUGUGCUGAGUGGAGGGGGCACCUCUGGCCGGAUGGCAUUCCUCAUGUCGGUGUCCUUUAAUCAGCUGAUGAAAGGUCUGGGACAGAAACCUCUUUACACCUACCUCAUUGCAGGUGGUGACAGGUCUGUGGUGGCCUCUAGGGAGGGGACAGAAGAUAGUGCCUUGCACGGGAUUGAGGAACUGAAGAAGGUGGCUGCCGGGAAGAAGAGAGUGAUUGUCAUUGGCAUUUCUGUGGGACUCUCUGCUCCCUUUGUGGCAGGCCAGAUGGACUGCUGCAUGAACAACACAGCUGUCUUCUUGCCAGUCCUGGUUGGCUUCAAUCCAGUGAGCAUGGCCAGAAAUGACCCCAUUGAAGACUGGAGUUCAACAUUCCGACAAGUAGCAGAGCGGAUGCAGAAAAUGCAGGAGAAACAGAAAGCUUUUGUGCUCAAUCCUGCCAUCGGGCCCGAGGGUCUCAGCGGCUCCUCCCGGAUGAAAGGUGGAAGUGCCACCAAGAUUCUGCUGGAAACCCUGUUAUUAGCAGCCCAUAAGACUGUGGACCAGGGCAUUGCAGCAUCUCAAAGAUGCCUCCUGGAAAUCUUGCGGACAUUUGAGCGAGCUCAUCAGGUGACCUACAGCCAAAGCCCCAAGAUUGCCACCCUGAUGAAGAGUGUCAGCACCAGUCUGGAGAAGAAAGGCCACGUGUACCUGGUUGGCUGGCAGACCCUGGGCAUCAUUGCCAUCAUGGAUGGAGUAGAGUGCAUCCACACCUUUGGUGCUGAUUUCCGAGAUGUCCGUGGCUUUCUCAUUGGUGAUCACAGUGACAUGUUUAACCAGAAGGCUGAGCUCACCAACCAGGGUCCCCAGUUCACCUUCUCCCAGGAGGACUUCCUGACUUCCAUCCUUCCCUCUCUCACGGAAAUCGAUACUGUGGUCUUCAUUUUCACCCUGGAUGACAACCUCACGGAGGUGCAGACUAUAGUGGAGCAGGUGAAAGAGAAGACCAACCACAUCCAGGCCCUGGCACACAGCACCGUGGGUCAGACCUUGCUGAUCCCUCUGAAGAAGCUCUUUCCCUCCAUCAUCAGCAUCACAUGGCCACUGCUUUUCUUUGAAUAUGAAGGGAACUUCAUCCAGAAGUUCCAGCGUGAGCUAAGCACCAAAUGGGUGCUGAAUACAGUGAGUACAGGUGCUCAUGUGCUUCUUGGUAAGAUCCUACAAAACCACAUGUUGGACCUUCGGAUUAGCAACUCCAAGCUCUUCUGGCGGGCGCUGGCCAUGCUGCAGCGGUUCUCUGGACAGUCCAAGGCUCGAUGCAUCGAGAGCCUCCUCCGAGCGAUCCACUUUCCCCAGCCACUGUCAGAUGAUAUUCGGGCUGCUCCCAUCUCCUGCCAUGUCCAGGUUGCACAUGAGAAGGAACAGGUGAUACCCAUCGCCUUGCUGAGCCUCCUAUUCCGGUGCUCGAUCACUGAGGCUCAGGCACACCUGGCUGCAGCUCCUUCUGUCUGUGAGGCUGUCAGGAGUGCUCUUGCUGGGCCAGGUCAGAAGCGCACUGCGGACCCCCUCGAGAUCCUAGAGCCUGACGUUCAGUGAACCCAUGUUUCUGGGUGGGUGAAAGGGGCCCAACCCUGCCCACUUCAGCCCAGCCCGCCCAAGGGGACUUGUGCCAGCAGAACAUGUGGGAGGAAGAAGCCCCGUUUCCAGGGCAUCCGCAGCCCAGGGUAGGGAGAAAUAUUCUCUCCACUUUGGGGGAGAGUUCUUGCUCUCGACCUAGUGGUUUCUACUCUCACCGACUUAUUCUGAUUUCAGAAAUAAAAUGAAAUGUCUUAUUUUGGAAA